AGAAAGACCAGAAAGAUCCGGGGGGUCUGCUCUGUGCGGUGAAGCUUCUCUUCUUGGCACCUGCCUGGCAUCGGAAGAGGGCCCCUUCUCCCUCCCUGGGCUUUUAUGUGGACACUGUAAUGCCUCAGUUUUCUUUCUUUCUUUUUGUUUUUGACACAGGGUCUCACUCUAUCACCCAAGCUGGAGUGCAGUGGCACCAUCUUAGCUCACCGCAGCCUCAAACUCCCCAGCUCGGGUGAUUCUUCCUGCCUCAGCCUCCUGAGUAGUAGCAGCUGGGACCACAGACGUCUGCCACCAAGCCCAGCUGCACCGCCAGUUCCGGGGAGGGCCCUGGGCCAGCGGCUGUCCGCCCCCCCUCCUUUAUAAAGUCCUGGCCUCGGGACAGCCCGCACAGCUGCCCAGCCUGCGGAGACGGGACAGCCCUGUCCCACUCACUCUUUCCCCUGCUGCUCCUGCCGGCAGCUCAGCUGGAACCAUGGGAGGCCGCGUCUUUCUCGUCUUUCUCGCAUUCUGUGUCUGGCUGACUCUGCCGGGAGCUGAAACCCAGGACUCCAGGGGCUGUGCCCGGUGGUGCCCUCAGGACUCCUCGUGUGUCAAUGCCACCGCCUGUCGCUGCAAUCCAGGGUUCAGCUCUUUUUCUGAGAUCAUCACCACCCCCAUGGAGACUUGUGACGACAUCAACGAGUGUGCAACACUGUCGAAAGUGUCAUGCGGAAAAUUCUCGGACUGCUGGAACACAGAGGGGAGCUACGACUGCGUGUGCAGCCCAGGAUAUGAGCCUGUUUCUGGGGCAAAAACAUUCAAGAAUGAGAGCGAGAACACGUGUCAAGAUGUGGACGAAUGUCAGCAGAACCCAAGGCUCUGUAAAAGCUACGGCACCUGCGUCAACACCCUCGGCAGCUACACGUGCCAGUGCCUGCCUGGCUUCAAGCUCAAACCUGAGGACCCGAAGCUCUGCACAGAUGUGAAUGAAUGCACCUCCGGACAAAACCCAUGCCACAGCUCCACCCACUGCCUCAACAACGUGGGCAGCUAUCAGUGCCGCUGCCGCCCGGGCUGGCAACCGAUUCCGGGGUCCCCCAAUGGCCCAAACAAUACCGUCUGUGAAGAUGUGGACGAGUGCAGCUCCGGGCAGCAUCAGUGUGACAGCUCCACCGUCUGCUUCAACACCGUGGGUUCAUACAGCUGCCGCUGCCGCCCAGGCUGGAAGCCCAGACACGGAAUCCCGAAUAACCAAAAGGACACUGUCUGUGAAGAUAUGACUUUCUCCACCUGGACCCCGCCCCCUGGAGUCCACAGCCAGACGCUUUCCCGAUUCUUCGACAAAGUCCAGGACCUGGGCAGAGACUACAAGCCAGGCUUGGCCAAUAACACCAUCCAGAGCAUCUUACAGGCGCUGGAUGAGCUGCUGGAGGCCCCUGGGGACCUGGAGACCCUGCCCCGCUUACAGCAGCACUGUGUGGCCAGUCACCUGCUGGAUGGCCUAGAGGAUGUCCUCAGAGGCCUGAGCAAGAACCUUUCCAAUGGGCUGUUGAACUUCAGUUAUCCUGCAGGCACAGAAUUGUCCCUGGAGGUGCAGAAGCAAGUAGACAGGAGUGUCACCUUGAGACAGAAUCAGGCAGUGAUGCAGCUCGACUGGAAUCAGGCACAGAAAUCUGGUGACCCAGGCCCUUCUGUGGUGGGCCUUGUCUCCAUUCCAGGGAUGGGCAAGUUGCUGGCUGAGGCCCCUCUGGUCCUGGAACCUGAGAAGCAGAUGCUUCUGCAUGAGACACACCAGGGCUUGCUGCAGGACGGCUCCCCCAUCCUGCUCUCAGAUGUGAUCUCUGCCUUUCUGAGCAACAACGACACCCAAAACCUCAGCUCCCCAGUUACCUUCACCUUCUCCCACCGUUCAGUGAUCCCGAGACAGAAGGUGCUCUGUGUCUUCUGGGAGCAUGGCCAGAAUGGAUGUGGUCACUGGGCCACCACAGGCUGCAGCACAAUAGGCACCAGAGACACCAGCACCAUCUGCCGUUGCACCCACCUGAGCAGCUUUGCCGUCCUCAUGGCCCACUACGAUGUGCAGGAGGAGGAUCCCGUGCUGACUGUCAUCACCUACAUGGGGCUGAGCGUCUCUCUGCUGUGCCUCCUCCUGGCGGCCCUCACUUUUCUCCUGUGUAAAGCCAUCCAGAACACCAGCACCUCACUGCAUCUGCAGCUCUCGCUCUGCCUCUUCCUGGCCCACCUCCUCUUCCUCGUGGCAAUUGAUCAAACCGGACACAAGGUGCUGUGCUCCAUCAUCGCCGGUACCUUGCACUAUCUCUACCUGGCCACCUUGACCUGGAUGCUGCUGGAGGCCCUGUACCUCUUCCUCACUGCACGGAACCUGACGGUGGUCAACUACUCAAGCAUCAACAGAUUCAUGAAGAAGCUCAUGUUCCCUGUGGGCUACGGAGUCCCAGCUGUGACAGUGGCCAUUUCUGCAGCCUCCAGGCCUCACCUUUAUGGAACACCUUCCCGCUGCUGGCUCCAACCAGAAAAGGGAUUUAUAUGGGGCUUCCUUGGACCUGUCUGCGCCAUCUUCUCUGUGAAUUUAGUUCUCUUUCUGGUGACUCUCUGGAUUUUGAAAAACAGACUCUCCUCCCUCAAUAGUGAAGUGUCCACCCUCCGGAACACAAGGAUGCUGGCAUUUAAAGCGACAGCUCAGCUGUUCAUCCUGGGCUGCACGUGGUGUCUGGGCAUCUUGCAGGUGGGUCCGGCUGCCCGGGUCAUGGCCUACCUCUUCACCAUCAUCAACAGCCUGCAGGGUGUCUUCAUCUUCCUGGUGUACUGCCUCCUCAGCCAGCAGGUCCGGGAGCAAUAUGGGAAAUGGUCCAAAGGGAUCAGGAAAUUGAAAACUGAGUCUGAGAUGCACACACUCUCCAGCAGUGCUAAGGCUGACACCUCCAAACCCAGCACGGUUAACUAGAAAAAUCUUCUGAAUAAGAUCUUCCCUCUUUGCCCGUGGAAAAUCUGAACAAUCUUUGAGCCAUCUAGAGGGGAAAGAAAAGACUUUGUUCUGUGUGUUUCAAGAAAUUCACCAUGUCAGCAAUAUGAAGGAUGUUAUGGAAGGCGUGCUAGGCAUUCAAUUCCUGCAGAAACCGGAAAUCUUCCAUGCCCUGCAAUGUGCUCAUCAAACUCUCAGCAUAUGGACGGCCAGCUGUGGCCCAUAUCUUGGUCACUCUGAAGCACAAUAUUUAUGAAGCUAUAGAACGUUAAGACCUCUUUCACAGCCUCUCCUUCCUACAAAGACUCCUCCAAAUCUUAAAAUGAAGCAGGAAAACGAGCCUAAGAGGACUUUCAUACCGACAACAUCUGAAAGGACUAGAAUGUUCACACCACGAUCUGGAUUUCUUAAUUUUUUGUUUUUGUUUUUGUUGUUCUCUAGUUCUACGGGUUUGAUUAUUUAGUCAUGUGAAAAAUAUUGAUUACUCACACAUAGAUCAAGAGAGACACGGCUCCUGCCUUCAUGGAGCUUUUAGGGGAAAAUGAAGUGGCUCUUGCAGCUAGAGUUGACUCAGAAGCCGAAAUUCCUAGAAAUCAGGUUUCUACUGCUAGGCAAUUGAAGUAUAAACUAUUUUAUAAACACUGUCUUCUUUCGUCUUCACACCAACAUGCAGAAAAGUUUCUAAUCUCAGAUCGGGGAUGUGCAACAAAUUCCAUUUCAAAGGAAUGACCUGCAAAACUCCUAAAUAUUCCAAGCAAAUGCCCUUAACCCUGUCUGUUAUCUGCUUUCCUUGAACAGAAAUUCUACAUGACCAUAAAACCUCGAAGAUGGGUAUGGCACAGUUCAUGCCCUGUAAUCCUAGCACUUUGGGAGGGUGAGGCAGGAGGAUGGCUCAAGCCCAGGAGUUUGAGACCAGUGUGGGCAACAGAGUGAGAACCAUCUCUACCCAAAAAAAAAAUUAAAAAUUAGCCAAGCAUGGUGAUGAUAUAGGAGUUAAGGAGAAAUCAUUUAGGCAAAUAGCAAGGGUAGGAAGUCCUCAGUAAGGUUUUCCAUUUAAUGAAAAGCAGCCCCCAAAAUCAUUUUCUUUUCUAACAAAGAACAGCCUGUAAAAUCGAGCUGCAGACAUAGACAAGCAAGCUGGAAGCUUCCACGGGUGAAUGCCGGCAGCUGUGCCAAUAGGAAAAAGCUACCUAGACUAGGCAUGUCCAAAAUGGCGGCUCCAAGUUCCCUUCUCUUUGCCAGCCAUGUGUACAGUAAAAAGCAGGCAACAUAGUGUCAGCCAAAGCUCAUUUGCAUAAUAAGAUUAGGGUGGGGUGGCCAGCUCACAUAGGGGUAGGCCCUAGGUAAAUCAGACACCGCCUUCUCAAGCCUGUCUAUAAAAUCUGGUACACUAUGACGAGGGUCAGAUUUCCCAUUCAGACGCCCCUCUCCCAUGCAAGAGAAAGAGCUGUUCUCCUUUCUCUUUCUUUUGCCUAUUAAACCUCUGCUCCUGGCCAGGCACAGUGGCUCACGCCUAUAAUCCCAGCACUUUGGGAGGCUGAGGUGGUCAGAUCACCUAAGGUCAGGAGUUCAAGACCAGCCUGGUCAACAUGGUGAAAUCUUGUCUCUAGUAAAAAUACAAAAAUAUAUGAAAUCUCACAUAGAUGAUAAUAUUAAGUUCCAAAAGCAACUCAACCUGGUAGAUUCUAAUUUUUUUUGAGGCAGGGUCUUGCUUUGUCACCCAUGCUGGAGUACAAUGGCACAAACACUGCUCACUGCAGCCUCGACCUCCCAAGGCCUAAGCAAUCCUCCUGCCUCAGUCCCCCUCCAGGUAUUUGAAACUACAGGUGUGUACCACCACACCGGGCUAAUUUUUGUAUUUUUUGUAGAGACGUGGGUCUCACUAUGCUGCCCAGGCUCAGGUCUUAAUCUCCUGAGCUCAGGCAAUCCGCAGGCCUCAGCCUCCCUAAGUGCGGGGAUUACAGGCUUGAGCCACUGCACCUAGCCUCUAUUUGUUUUACAAAAGAGAAAUUGAGAUCCUGAAUGUUAAGUGACUUGCCUGAGGCCAUCCCACUAACAGGAGCCAGGGUUAGGAUUCAAACCCCAUCCAACUGGUCCCAGAGCUGGAGCUUCUUGCACUGCCCUACACUACCUACCAUCUCCAUCCUCUGGGCACCUUUUUAUAAGAACCAAAACAUUACAGAGCAUUGCUUUGUCAACUCAGCUGGGAACAUUUCCCAGUGCAACUCACAUUUUUCACUGCUCUGUGCCUGUCCGUAUAAGCUCAAUGAGUAUUGAUUUAGGGGCUUUGGAGAACUUUGAAUGCUACCCCCCAAGUAACCAUUGUUGGCAACCUGGUACCUCUACUUUUAGCCAUUUCUCCUUCUCUAUAAAUAGUGCAGAAGUAACCCACUUGGUAACAGGCAUCCUUGCCAAGCCUCCACCACUAGGUCAGUGUAAGAAUUAAAGAAAGAGGAAAGAAACACAAAAAGUGGCUUGAUGGUUAAGACAGGUUUAUUUUAGAGAAAACACACCUGAGAGGGGCUGCUGGCUGAAUUAGGUUAGAGUCUUUUCUACAGACUAAGAGUGUUUAAGGAUUUAGGGUGGGAGAGUUUCUUAGAGGCUUGGACUGCUUCUGUGUUUUUUUUGUUGUGCUUAUAUGGGAGGGAGAGUGGUGUGUUUGCUUUUAUACAUUUUUCUGCAGCUGUAGGCAUACCCCCCAAGUCUGCUUUUAGCUUCCCUAUUUUAGUGCACCUGGAGGGAAAGGAAUGUGCUUAUUAAGGCCCACUGUUUUACUGGGGCCCAUUGUAUGAGGGUGAAGUUUGGCAGUUACCCAAGAGACUUUUCCUCCACCUUCCUCUGUGCCCGAGCUGUUUUAUCUGCAUUUUACUGUCUGCUUUUUUUGGCUGCUUAUAGUUUUUAAAAAAGUAAUUUCCUUAAAUCCAGAAGGCUAAAAAUGAAGCUGAAACUUAAAGUGGCGGUGUUUGUCCAAAAUAACGGGGCUCCUGCUCUGCCAGUCAGUACCCUCAAGUCACUCCUGAUCCUCAACCUCCAUGCCUAAGGCUGGUUCAAGAGACCACAUAAUAUCUGCCUUUUAUUACAUACAUGAUGGGUGCAUGGGAUUCUGCGUGCCCUUUGCUUGAUAUAGACUGCUAAGGUGAGAUGGGGAAUAUCAGAGUCAGCUGCUGCUUGAGGAAGCAGAACACACAGCUGGAGGCUUGGAACAUGUGGGUCCCUAUGAGUGUAGAGCCCAUAUCCCCAUAGAGUCUACCUAGAGCAGGGGUCGCCAAAUGUUUUCUUAAAGAGCCUGAUAGUGUAUAUGUUAGGCUUUGUGAGCCAGGUAUUUACAGCAACUCAAUUCUACCACUGUGGUAUGAAAACAGCUAUAGACAAUCAUAAAUGAAUGAUCAUGGCUAUGUUUUAAUAAAACUUUACAGACACUGAACUUGAACUUCCAUUGUGAUAUGAAAACAGCUAUAGACAAUCAUAAAUGAAUGAUCAUGGCUAUGUUUUAAUAAAACUUUAUGGACACUGAGCUUGAACUUCAUAUAUCAGUCAUGUGACACAAAAUAUCAUUCUUCUUUUUAUUUGUUUUCACCCAUUUGAAAAAUGUAAAAACUAUUCUUAGCUGUACAGAAACAGAUGGUGGGUCAGAUUUGACUCACUGCCCAUAGUUUCCAGACCAUGAUGUUCAGGUUCAUGGAAGCACUUCACUCUACACUAAUUUAUUCAUCCAUUCAUCACAUAUGUGAUGAGCACAUACAGACACACCUCAGAGAUAUUGCAGGCUCCACUCCAGAUCACCACAAUAAUGUGAAUAUUGCAAUAAAGCAAGUCAUACACAUUU